AGACGCCGGCGCCGCGCAGCCGGGCCCGCUCCUCCUCCGCUCCGCCAGUGUCCGGCCGCGGGCCGGCCUUAGUGACUGGGGCGGCGGGCCCCGGGGCCGCGGCGUGGGGCGGGCAGGCGGACGCCGGCCGCGGGCUGCUUUCGUCGGCUCCCAAGCUCUCCCGGAGCGAGCAGCCGCCCGCGAGCCGCCGCGGAGCCUCCUCGCCCGCUCCCGCCGGCGAGCAAGAUGAUGUGCGAGGUGAUGCCGACCAUCAGCGAAGCAGAAGGCCCCCCUGGAGGAGGUGGAGGCCAUGGUUCCGGCUCCCCUUCACAGCCAGAUGCAGAUUCACAUUUUGAACAGUUGAUGGUCUCCAUGCUAGAAGAAAGGGACCGCCUUCUUGAUACACUGAGAGAGACUCAAGAAACGCUGGCCUUAACCCAGGGGAAGUUACACGAGGUUGGUCAUGAAAGAGAUUCCUUGCAGAGACAGCUCAACACGGCACUUCCACAGGAGUUCGCAGCACUUACUAAAGAACUCAAUGUAUGCAGGGAACAGCUCCUUGAAAGGGAAGAAGAAAUUGCUGAACUGAAAGCAGAAAGGAAUAACACCAGGCUGCUGUUAGAGCAUUUGGAAUGCCUUGUCUCCAGGCAUGAGCGGUCUCUUAGGAUGACCGUGGUGAAGAGACAAGCGCAGUCUCCAGCAGGCGUGUCCAGCGAAGUGGAAGUGCUGAAAGCACUGAAGUCCUUAUUUGAACACCACAAAGCUCUGGAUGAAAAGGUGAGAGAGCGAUUACGAGUAGCACUUGAAAGAUGUAGUUUGUUAGAAGAGGAAUUAGGUGCCACACACAAAGAGCUAAUGAUUCUUAAAGAACAGAAUAAUCAGAAAAAAACUCUAACAGAUGGAGUGCUGGACAUAAACCAUGAACAAGAAAAUACACCAAGCACGAGUGGAAAGAGAUCUUCUGAUGGUUCUUUAAGCCACGAGGAAGACCUUGCUAAAGUAAUUGAGCUCCAAGAAAUCAUAAGUAAGCAGUCAAGGGAACAGAGCCAAAUGAAAGAACGCCUGGCUUCCCUUUCCAGUCAUGUGACAGAACUGGAAGAGGAUCUGGACACGGCUAGAAAAGAUCUCAUCAAAUCUGAAGAAAUGAACACAAAAUUGCAACGAGAUGUCCGUGAAGCCAUGGCCCAAAAGGAAGAUAUGGAAGAGAGAAUCACUACUCUUGAAAAACGCUACCUCGCUGCACAGCGUGAAGCCACAUCUGUGCAUGACCUCAAUGAUAAACUUGAAAAUGAAAUUGCAAAUAAAGAUUCUAUGCAUCGACAGACUGAAGAUAAAAACCGCCAGUUACAGGAGCGCUUGGAAUUGGCAGAGCAAAAGCUGCAACAGACACUGAGGAAGGCAGAGACGCUCCCGGAGGUGGAGGCGGAGCUGGCCCAGAGGGUGGCAGCGCUUUCCAAGUCUGACCUUUUGUCUUCUGGGAGCUCUGCUGCUAAGGAAGCUAAACUGUUGGAACUUACUUCCAAGCUUAGGAAGGCUGAAGAGAGACACGGCAACAUUGAAGAAAGGUUACGACAGAUGGAAGCACAGUUGGAGGAGAAGAAUCAAGAACUGCAGCGGGCAAGGCAAAGAGAAAAAAUGAACGAAGAACAUAAUAAACGUUUAUCAGACACUGUUGACAAGCUGCUUUCAGAAUCUAAUGAGAGGCUUCAACUUCAUCUUAAAGAGAGAAUGGCUGCUUUGGAAGAUAAGAACUCUCUUUUAAGAGAAGUUGAAAGUGCAAAAAAGCAGUUAGAAGAAACACAACACGAUAAGGAUCAGCUUGUCCUAAACAUUGAAGCACUGAGGGCUGAACUAGACCACAUGAGACUAAGAGGUGCUUCACUUCAUCAUGGCCGACCCCACUUGGGCAGUGUCCCAGAUUUCAGGUUCCCCAUGGCAGACGGCCACACAGACUCCUACAGCACCAGUGCAGUGCUGCGGCGCCCACAGAAAGGCCGGCUGGCAGCCCUGCGAGAUGAGCCUUCCAAGGUACAAACUCUUAAUGAGCAGGAUUGGGAACGUGCCCAGCAAGCUAGUGUCUUGGCAAAUGUAGCACAAGCAUUCGAGAGUGAUGCUGACGUGUCUGAUGGUGAAGAUGACAGGGACACUCUCCUCAGCUCAGUUGACCUGCUAUCGCCCAGCGGGCAGGCCGACGCGCACACACUAGCCAUGAUGCUUCAGGAGCAGCUGGACGCCAUCAACAAAGAGAUCAGGUUGAUUCAGGAAGAAAAAGAAAAUACAGAGCAGCGGGCAGAGGAGAUUGAAAGUCGAGUUGGCAGUGGAAGUCUAGACAAUCUUGGUCGUUUUAGAUCAAUGAGCUCCAUUCCCCCCUACCCUGCUUCCUCGCUUGCUAGCUCCUCCCCUCCGGGCAGUGGGCGCUCCACCCCACGAAGGAUCCCUCACAGCCCAGCUCGGGAAGUGGACAGACUGGGCGUCAUGACCCUUCCAUCUCCAGAUUCAUUUUUAAUCCAGACCUCAGGUCCCCAUCAGUCAGUAGUUUACUCAUCCACCUCCCCUCCCAGUUCCACCCCAUGCUAUAGCGAUUCUUCACAGCAUGCUCAGCCUAGUGAUUUAAGGAAACAUCGUAGAAAGUUGCCACCUUCCAGAGAAGAGGUACGAGAUGACAAGACAACCAUAAAGUGUGAAACCUCCCCGCCUUCCUCCCCGAGAGCCCUUCGGUUAGACCGGCUGCACAAAGGGGCGCUGCACACCGUCAGCCACGAGGACAUCAGGGACAUAAGGAACUCCACAGGCUCCCAGGAUGGUCCCGUGAGCAACCCCAGCAGUAGCAACAGUAGCCAGGACUCGCUCCACAAAGCCCCAAAGAAGAAAGGCAUUAAGUCCUCCAUUGGCCGCUUGUUUGGCAAGAAAGAAAAGGGCCGACCUGGACAAACUGGCAAAGAAGCAUUAGGACAAGCUGGUGUUUCCGAGACGGAUAACUCAUCUCAGGAUGCCUUGGGACUUAGCAAAUUGGGGGGACAGGCUGAAAAAAAUCGUAAACUUCAAAAAAAGCAUGAAUUGCUGGAGGAAGCCCGGAGACAAGGUUUACCUUUUGCCCAAUGGGACGGGCCAACGGUUGUGGUCUGGCUAGAGCUCUGGGUUGGGAUGCCAGCCUGGUAUGUGGCUGCCUGCCGAGCAAACGUGAAAAGCGGGGCCAUCAUGUCGGCCCUGUCCGACACAGAGAUCCAGCGUGAGAUUGGCAUCAGCAACCCCCUGCACAGGCUGAAGCUGAGGCUGGCCAUCCAGGAGAUCAUGUCGCUGACCAGCCCGUCUGCCCCGCCCACAUCUAGAACGACCACAGGAAAUGUCUGGUUAACACACGAAGAGAUGGAAACGCUCGCAGCCACGCCGCAAACGGAAGAUGAGGAGGGAAGCUGGGCUCAGACACUCGCCUAUGGGGACAUGAACCACGAGUGGAUCGGCAACGAGUGGCUCCCCAGCCUGGGCCUCCCCCAGUACCGCAGCUACUUCAUGGAGUGCCUUGUAGACGCCAGGAUGCUGGACCACUUGACCAAGAAAGACCUUCGAGGGCAGCUGAAAAUGGUCGACAGUUUUCACAGAAACAGUUUCCAGUGUGGAAUUAUGUGCCUGAGAAGGUUAAAUUAUGACCGGAAAGAACUGGAAAGAAAAAGAGAAGAAAGUCAGAGUGAAAUAAAAGACGUGCUUGUUUGGAGCAAUGAUCGAGUGAUUCGCUGGAUCCUGUCAAUUGGCCUUAAAGAAUAUGCAAACAAUCUUAUAGAGAGUGGUGUUCACGGAGCACUUCUGGCCUUAGAUGAAACCUUCGACUUCAGUGCACUGGCACUGCUGUUACAGAUCCCGACGCAGAACACACAGGCUCGUGCUGUCUUGGAAAGAGAAUUUAACAACCUUUUGGUCAUGGGGACUGAUAGAAGGUUUGAUGAAGAUGAUGAUAAAAGCUUUAGGAGAGCACCUUCAUGGAGAAAAAAGUUUAGACCAAAGGACAUUCGUGGCUUAGCUGCUGGGUCAGCAGAGACUCUCCCUGCAAACUUCCGGGUGACUUCUUCUAUGUCUUCCCCCUCUAUGCAGCCAAAGAAGAUGCAGAUGGACGGCAAUGUAUCAGGAACACAGAGGUUGGAUUCUGCUACAGUCAGGACUUACUCCUGCUAAAGUCUCCUGUUGUUUACCCACACUACUUCUACAGAUGAUUAUGCAGCAUUUGAAUCCAACAAAGACUACAUUUUGGAAUCCAGUGGAAUCUUUAAUCUUGUUAAUACUUGUUAUAUGGACCCUAAGAUAUUUUAUUACAGAGUUUUUAAUUAGUGAAAAAUUCAUGAAUACCAUAGAGAAAAUAUUUUAGAAUUUAAUGUUUCUUAUAUUUAUGUAAACUUAUGACUCUUCAUUUAUAUAGUUACUUACUUUUUCAUGUAUAUCCAGGCUAUAAAUAUCCUUUCAAAUCAUGUUCUUAUACCUAAUUUUAGUCUUUCAAAUGAAUGUACUGUAAUGCUUGUAUGUAUAAAUCCUAUGAAUAGAGGGCUUUUGUAAAUUAUGCAUUUAUUGUAAUUAUCAUUAAUUUUUUAAUGAUAAACCAUGACAAAGGAUUUUACGUUUAUAAAAUUAUGACAGAAGCCAUGUGCAUUAUCCUUUACGGACGCAGCCUAGCUCUACAGCAAUCAUCCUGAAAUAAGCAUACCUAAUUUCAAGCAAUUGUUGUAUUUUCAUGACUGACCUUAACUGUACUUUUUCUAGCAAGAGAUGCUUUAUUCUGCAGCAUGAACAGAUUUAAAAUGGCUGGUGUUAAAUAUCAGCUCCUAAUAAGAUGUGGACUGAAAACACUAUCACAACACUAUGAGAAGCCCCUAGCACUGGUUAACGCUUUCCUAGCCUAGUCUCUGGAUUUGGGGAGCUUGUCUUCAGUGGCUGAGACUGUGAGCUGGGAGCAGUUCUCUCAGCUGGAGAGACUCGGGAUGGGGUAACCUGGGGACCAGUCUAGCCCCUGCACCCUCUUCCCUGCCUCUGCUCCUUGGGAGCGGGUGGAGAGACACCCAUGUGGCUCCCCUUAGGGCCAGCACCAAGCACCACGCUCUCAUCCUGCAAGUCGGCGCACACAGUGGAUGAAGGCAGGAGACCCAGAAAGCAGUGCAGUGCAGCUCUAAUAAAGGCCUUAUUUUUCUUAUGUAAAUCAUCUUUUUACAUUUGUUUGUAAACAUGUUUAAAGAACGAACCUAGUGGGACAUUUUUAGACUUUGAUGCUCUAGCCAUUUUGGAUUGUGUAAGUUGCAGAUGUGGCUUUUACUUUUUAAAUGGCAUAUUAACAAGCCAGCAAAGUGUGUCAGACCAUGGCGUGGUAUUUAUUGUGCAGCAGAUCCAGAGACAGAGGCAGCCUGUCUUUUCAGUUGGUUUCUGCUUUUAAUUUACUUGUACAAUUCAUUGUUACUGUUCUGUUUUUCUAUUAAUCUUUUGUCAACUUCCUGAUUAUGUAACAAAGUAUGUACAGUCUACUUUUGAACUAUUUUUAUCACAGUAUUAUUUAUUGCUUUCUUUCAAUAAAGUACUGAAGCAUUUUCCACUGCCAA